ACAGGUUCUUGCUCUGUCACCCAGGCCAGAGCACAGUGGUGCAAUCACAGCGCACUGCAGUGCAGCCUCAAUCUCCUGGGCUCAAGCGAUCCCCCACCUCAGCCUCUUGAGUAGCUGGGGUUAUAGGCACCCACCACCACACUUGGCUAAGUUUUAAAAAAUUUUUUUAUAGAGACAGGGUCUCACUAUGUUGACUAGGCUGGUCUUGAACUCCUGGGUUCAAGCAGAUCCUCCUGGCUCAGCCUCCCAAAGUGCUGAGAUUACAGGCAUGAACCACCACACCCUCCUGGUACCUGCAUUUUGAAAAUGUUUCAUUGCCAAGCCUGCAGGGAAGUCUGCCCUUUUUUUAUUAGAAAAUGAAGAGCUAAUUCUGAAAUAUGCCUACUAAAUAUGCAUAUCUCAAGCACUUUAAAAGGAUGUAGGGUGAAAUAGUCUGUUCCUGAAGCAAAUAUCACUGUGUGUUCAUUCCAUUAUUUCCGUAGCUUUUCUGUGGCUUUUGAUAAGUUGUGUAGAAUGUAUUAAGUCUCAUCUGAAAAUGUAUAUUAAAGAUUGUUCUUUUAAUUUAAAAUGAUUUGUCCAAGGUACUUGACUUAAUGAUUCAAGAUUUAAUGAGCCGUGACACUUUUAGUAACACCGUCUCAAUCUUUCAGAUUUUAUAAAAGAUAUUAAAGUUUUCAGAAAGUUGAGAAUGGUCUUUUGUAAUGUAUUUUAAGAUAGUUAAGAAUAGAGUUUAUAUAAUUAAGAUUAGGAUUUGUAUUGCAAAAACUCCCUUCAAGACGCAUUUUGGGCCUUUAUGAGCGAGUAAUCAUGACAGGACAGAGUGGCUUCACCCACAGUUUUGUGGUUAAUAUUUGCAAGUCGUUUAUUUAACAAGGUUGAAAAGAGGCUUCCUGGUGUCUUUUAUAAUUAUCCUUUUCUGGGGACCAACUUAUAAAGUAAAAAAUACCUGGUGGCAUUAUCUUUGCUUCAGAUGUAUUAUGUUUAUGGAAUUGGAAAUGUUUGAUUUCUUAGUGUGUGUGUAUCAGUGGAUUAUGUAGUUUAAAAUGUUUGCAUCUGUAUUGCAUGCAUAAACAUGUCCGUUUCCAAGUGUGGCCUUUAAAUACUCAGGGUUUUGUGGCCGGGCACGGUGGCUCACGCCUGUAAUCCCAGCACUUUGGGAGCCCGAGGCAGGCAGAUCAUGAGGUCGGGAGUUCGAGACCAGCCUGGCCAAUAUGGUGAAACCCAGUCUCUACUAAAAAUAUAAAAAUUAGCCGGGUGUGGUGGCGUGUGCCUGUAAUCCUAGCUAUUCGAGAGGCUGAGACAAAAGAAUUGCUUGAACCCUGGAGGCGGAGGUUGCAGUGAGCCAAGAUUGUGCCACUGCACUCCAGCCUGGAUGACAGAGUGAGACUCCAUCUCAAAUAAAAUAAAAUACAAUAAAAUAAAAGACUGAGGGUUUUUUAAAAGGUCAUAAUAGAAAAAUUUUAUGUGUUUUAAUUGUUUAAAUGUUUUCUUCGGGAUUAAAAAAACCUGAAUGUAUUCUGGGAAAAUGUUAAAUGGAUGCAACACUAUAAGAUUUUCCACAGAAAUAUGUUAUUCACCGUGAAGCACAAUGGGAAGGCUCCAUUAGCACUUUAGAUGGUAUCAUAACUUUGGAAAAACCAUUUCACCAUGCGAGUAUUUACAAAAACUGAAGCUGUCCCUGUCAGGUUUUGACAGAGCUUAGCUAUAUAGGUAGUAAGUGACGCAGUGCCAAAACCAGUCUUAAAUUACCUAUGUUGUCAAUAUGCAGAUUUUCUCUAUUUAGUAUUUAAGCUAUGAAUUUACCAAUCUGAGUAACUUGAAAUGCAGUAUCAUAAAAAGAAUCAGAUCUACCAAACUGAAAAUGUGUGCGUAUCUAAAGUAGUUUCUUUUCUUGAUUUUGGUUAAGUUAACAGGAGUAUCUUCACAUCUGUAAUUUCUGGUAACUUAAUGAGAACACACUGAACUUUUGGGUCACAAUAAAUUUUCCCAUUAUGUAAAAUAUUUUACACACCGGUUGACUCAUUGUGAAUUGUGAGUCGACAUGAUUCUCUUCCUGCGGAAAACAGAAACACAUGCUGGCCGGGCGCUGUGGCUUAUGCCUGUAAUCCCAGCACUUUGGGAGGUGAAGGCGGGUGGAUCACCUGAGGUCAGGAGUUCGAGACCCAGCCUGACCAACAUGGAGAAACCCUGUCUCUACUAAAAAUACAAAAUUAGCCGGGCAUGGUGGCACAUGCCUGUAAUUCCAGCUACUGGGGAGGCUGAGGCAGGAGAGUUGCUUGAACCCGGGAGGCAGAGGUUGCGGUGAGCCGAGAUCACGCCAUUGCACUCCAGCCUAGGCAACAAGAGUGAAACUCCAUCUCAAAAAAAAAAAAAAGAAACACAUGUUAUUGUAAUGAUGAUUUGAGCCAAUUACAGGAUUGUGCUUAUGUUACCACAUUGACUAGGUGCUUUCUGUGAGUUGGGUUGUUGAAGAGUUUGAGGUAGACAGAUGGCAGUGGGUGGGAAUGAGCGGGGAGCUUUUGUUAGGUUUAGGGAAUGUGGUCUUUCCACCAUCAUUUAGUUGUUUAUUUUAUGCAUAGGCUUAUUUUCGUUCUUGUGAGCAUUAUGUUGAGUUAAUGUGUUUUCUUUGACCUCAAACCUUCUGAAAUGUUUCUGGGUCUUAAAGAUUCAGGUAUUAUUUAUUUCAUAGUAGACAGAAUCAAGUAAAUGAAUACUUUCUUGGGGGAGAGUGUUGAUAAGUUCCAUAGCGACACCUCUCCCUCAUGAUUAAAAGUGCUACAUUUGCACAAAUAUGUGACUUAUAUUUUAUAUUAAAAUUAAGAUCAACUUUUUUCUUGAGAAGUUGUUGAACUUUUAGAUUUGGGAGAGGGGGAGUUCUCACAGGAAUUAUGAAUUGUUUUGACUAGUGAGAAGCUUAUUUAACAUUUUUGGAAGGAGUACCCCAAAAGUAAUGCAUCUUUUGGCAUAGUGGAAACUUGCAGUAACGUUUUCUUGUUGUUUUUUAAUUGAUUGGGUGACCUGCAUCUCAUUAAGUGGUGUCUAUUGGAUGUUUGGCCUUUGGCUUGAUUGUGUCCGCUUUUAAAAAAUAACUUUAUUGAAAUCGUCACAUUCCAUACAAUUACCUAUUUAAAGUGUCCAUGUCUGUGGUUUUUAGUAUAUUCACAGAGUUGUGCAGCCAUUGCCUACUUUGGACAUUCUAUGGAAAUGCGGUUGACAGGAUGUGUUUUCUGUGUGCAGUCUCUGUCACUAAGCACCAUAUUUUCAUUCAUAUUGUGCAUGUAUGCAUCGGUUGUUCCUUGUUAAUGUCGAAUAUUAUUCCAUUGUGUGGAUGUUCCACAUUUUAUGUAUUUGUUAGUCCAUUGAUAGACGUUUGGGUUGUUUCUACUUUUUGGCUGUUGUGUGAUAGCGCUGCUGUGAACAUUCAUGUACAGGUUUUUGUGUGGACAUGUCAUUUCUCUUGGGAAUAUACCUAGGUUGUUUGUAUCUGCUUUUGCUGCUUCUUUUACCUACAGUUCAGAUUCCCAUUUAUGUUUGUACAGACAGUUUGCUACUUGUGACUGGGGCUUGUUUGACCUUUGUUGCUGACCUAGCGACUUCUUGUGUCAUGUUUAAAGCCCCUGAGACCCUCUGUUGCCUAGAGAAACAGGCAGAAUUGCAGUCUCUUUCCUUCCUAAGACCAGAUCACAUCUGGUGGUCAUGAAAUGGUCUUAUCCUGUAUAGAUUUUUGGUAAAUAAGUAUGUAUCUAAGCCAAAUAAAUUUUGUGUGUAUUUUAUAUUAUUUUUCUUCUCUCUGCUUCCUCUUGGGGACAUCCUUUGUUCUGUGGCCCCAGUGGCACCUAGAGUGAAUAUGAAUGAUUUGUCUAUGUUUUCCCUUCAGGCGGAAUGCCGAUUACUUGGAUUUUUUCUUGUUAAUUUUGGUGACUGAGUUGCCUGUUUUUGAAGUGAAAAAUACCUGCAGAUAGUAGGGUUGCCCUUUAGCAUUUUAAGUGUCUAAAUGAGACCUAUUGGGAUGUUUCCAUAGUUUGCAUCAAAUUCAUGUAAAUGCGCGUUAAUGAUGUUAGCUAGUCUGCCUGAGCUAAAUUACUAAUUUCAUUACUACUAUUUAAUAAAGGGGCAGGAUUUGCCAUGGUCAUUCUAGUUAAUGGUAAGAGCCCUGUAGGUCUCUCAUCAUAUAUCUAAGCUGAAUUAAGGUUGAAAAUAUUACUGAGUGCCUUGUGGCUCUAUUUGGUAACAGUCAUGCCUUACAUUUUGAGACAGCUAAUCCUUUUACACACCAGGUGACUCAUGUGAAUUGUGAGUAGACACGAUUCUCUUCCUGCAGAAAGAGAAUGCAUUCAGUCAGUUGAAAAUCAACAUCAUGUGGUUUGUAGGAUAGGUCUUACUCCUUUCUUAGACAAGGAAUCUGGGAUCCAGAAGGAGUGAGCGGUUGGUUAGGAGGAGUCAGUGCCAGAGGGAGGCAGCAUGCCCUUUCUGCUCUGCCCACGCUGUGAGGACACCGGGCCGUGCCUUCGCCAGGAGGAGGUCAUGCCAAGUCCAAAGCGUCAGGCCGCUCAGAGCCAAGCAGCUUUGCUGGAGCACCCACUGGUGCACUUGGAAAGUGAUUUCUCCUGUUAAAGCCUCGCUGCCACCUCAACUGUAAACUGGAGACAGUAGGAAGCCACCUUCACAGGCCUGCGGGGACCUGGCACCCGUGCACCAAACCUUGCUGCCCUUAAUCAGAUGGUCGAAUUGAGAGGCAGUUGGAAGGGUCCUGUGGUGUGCUCCUUCUGGGACCUUCUGCCACCCCUUGGAGGCAGGUUGCGCCCCUGCCCGUCUCUUCCCACCAGUGGACACUCCCUUCAGCCCUGGGCCAGCUGUGGGGCCCUCCUCUGUAGGCGCUGGCUGUUCCAGGAGGCACAAGAGUGUUGGUGUGGGACCUUCCCACUGCUCGAGAUCCCCCACGGAGAGCCCACUCAGGCUACGCUUGGGCUUCUGGCCGUGUGGGUCAGCGUCACAGGACGGACAGAUCAAUGGGGGAAGAGUCAUCCUGCAGCGCUGCCACCACUGGAGGCUGGUGAGAGUGGCGCUGCCACAGAGAACAAGCCUUGAUCCCUGACUUGAAAGUCAGAGUUCUUCUGGAACUUCUGUGGGGAGUGCCCAGAGUGGCACCUAAAUACGUCUAGAAGCGCUUGAUGAAAGUUCCUCUGAGGCUUUUAAACUGCUUGAGUGAGUCUCUCUGAAGCACGGUGAUGGCAAAAGGAAACCACCUCACGCUACCUCUUUGUGCCUUCUCUUCUCUCCUCAUCUCCUGUAGGCCGUAGGUGUUCCCUGUCAGGAAUUUACGCGGAGGCAUGUCUGCUGUGGCCAAAUGUGUUCAUUCAUUCAUAUCUCACAGUAAGAGGGAAGGAUGGGGGAGGAAGACUGCUGUAUUUCCUUAAAAGUUUUUCUGUAACUCGAAUCCCUCCCACCCCCGUGAGGUAACAACGUCUUUUCCAGUUGGUGUCAGUGAACUCUGUUUUGGGUAUCUACAAAAGCAGAAGGGGAGGUUAGGAUGUGGCUGGAGGAGGCUGGUUCCUGGGUGUAAAUCCUGGCUCUUCUGCUUGAACUGACUGUGCCUCAGCAUCCUCGUCUGUCUGGUGGAGCCGCCUCACAGAGGAACAAGUGAGUUGUGCGUGUGGAGCAGGUGGCUGACAUGUGGUGAGUCCUCCAGGAAUGUGGCAGCAGAAGGAACACGUUGAGCACCGCAGAUACCACCCUGACCGCCACUGCAGGGCUUCUGUGCGGGGGCAGCUGCAGAGCCGCCGCUUCAGGACAGCAUGGGAGCUGCUGGAGGUCGGGGGAGCUCAGGGAAAGGGCCUUGCUGCCAGGGGUGGGAAGGGAGUCAGUGAAGACGUCCUGGAGGAGAAGAUUCCAGAGCCUGAGAUGUGAAGUAGGUUAGGUAGCCAGAGACAAGGCAAAGAAGGGCCAUUUUCAUCAGAGAACAGCAUAACAUUGGCAGAGGUCUGACAUGUCAUUUCCUGUUACUAGAAUUGGGGAGUGACCAGUAGAUUCUUUAAUUUGUUUAUUCAUUCGUGCAGUCCUUCACCUCACACCUGUUCAGGGUCCGGCUGGGCUCUGGACAUAGGGUGGAAGAAAACCAUCUGAGCAGAGGCCGCGUGGACUGUCACCUCUGUCAGGGGUGCCAGGGCUGCCAAAGGACAGCUGUUACUUAUGGGUGGCGGCGUGGUGAGGUCGCACAACACAGAGCUGCCCUGCUGUGUCCAUGCCCUGGUGCCUCCCCGUGGUCACCAUGUGCCUUGGGCAAAUGGAGGCCUCAGGUCCCAGACAUAGGCUCUGUCAGUGGUGGUGGCGGUGGCUGUACCUGCUCCGGGCUGCUGUGAGGGAGGGACGGGCUCCGGCCACAGGCGUGCAAGGUCCCCUUGCAGAGGACCUCCCGCACCUGCUGAGGAAUGUGUACAGCCAUCUGGAGGGUGUUCUCCCCCUGGCCCUCCCUGUAGUCCAGCUGAGUCCACGUCCUUCAGCCCCUUUUCAAUGUUCCUUUCUCACAGAACCUUGUCCUGGAGGUGCACUCGGGCCCGGGUUCUUCCUCCUGUGCGGUGCCAAGCCCUCCUCCACCACGCAUGAUGGUGUGUUUUCCAUGACUCUUCCUCCUAGAGCACCGGUGCCCGCCCUGACGGCGGUUCCCCACAGUCAGAUUGAGUAUCCCUUAUCUGAAAUGCUUGGGACUAGAAGUGUUUCAGAUUCUGAUCUUUUCGGAUUUUGGCAUAUUUGAAUAUGCAUAAUUGGAUAUCUUGGGGAUGAGACUUAAGUGUAAACACAAAAUUCUUUUCAUAUACACCUUAUACACAUAGCCUGAAGGUAAUUUUAUGCAAUAUUCUUAAAUAUUUUGUGCAUGAAACAGAGUUUUGACUGUGACCCGUCACGUGAGGUCAGUUGGGGAAUUUUCCUCUUGUGGUGGUAUGUUGGUACUCAGAAAGUUUCGGAUUUUGGAGCAGUUUGGAUUUUUGGAUUAGGGAUGCUCCAUUUGAAUAUUCUUUUUAUAUACAGCACAUGGUCAGUGCUCACUAAACUUAGUAUUGCAUGAAUGAAUGAAAACCAAAGGUCAUUUACUAAGCGUGCUACUAUUUCAGAAGCCUCUUUUUCCUGAUUUGGUUCUAUGGUCAGUGGUUUAAUAUUUCAAGUGCUCUGACCACGUAAUGGUUGUUACCACACUGUGAAGGUGGCUGGGUGUUCAGUGAUUGCUGCCCACAGAGGACCUGGAAGUGCUUGCUGUACUUGGUUUUCUGGAAUGGAAAUCAUGGCUCAUUCCCAGGAGCCCCUCAGCAGGGGCUUUGAGUCUGGUGCUAAGCAGCAGAUGUGCAGAUUCCCGCAGGGCGUACCUGAGCCCGGAGAGGGGGCGUCGUAGCGCACAGCGCACUCGUUUCCGCAUUCCCACCCCGCACGGCCAGUUGUCACAGCCAUCCUCCAGUAAAAAACACAAACCAGUCAACCUCUAGGAGACAGGUAGGAAAUCUAGAAGAAGCCUCAGGUGUUCACAGCAUUUUUUAAAGAUUCUUUAAAAAUCUUCGUGAUUGGAAAGACUGCUUCCUGUGCCAGAGAGUCUCUCUCCAGCGCUUUUGCUUCUGAGGUUGGUAGCUUUCAGAAAGACUGCAAUGCAGCGGUUACCAAAGUCCUUGUUAAUAUGGAAACAACUCGUGGUGAAGCCUUUUGCUCCCCUUCACAACUGCUGACUGUUGCCUGCAGUCGGAAGGAGGAGAUAAUGAAGGUAAUACUCCUCCGGACCUGGCAGUUUAGUGAUUAGAACGUACGCGAUUCUGUGAAUGCUGUGGCUGGCACAGCAUGUCCUGCAGCAGCUCUGUCAACUUACUGAUGCAGUGGGCUUCCUGGGAACGUGAAGCUGAAGAUGUCUUUGCAGUUUGUGCACGAUAAUUUUGUUUUCAUCUCUGUGUUCAGAUGGUGGAUUAUAAGAAGAUGAGGAAAAUGAGGCCCAAAGAAGUGAUGCCACUUGGUUAAGGUCCCAGAGCAGGUCAGAAUCAGACCUAGGAUCAGAAACCUGGCUCCUGGCUCCUGGCUCCCUACUCUUCUAAGGAUCGCUGUCCUGACAGAAGAGAACUCCUCUUUCCUAAAAUGGAGUCGAGUAAAAAGAUGGACUCUCCUGGCGCGCUGCAGACUAACCCGCCGCUAAAGCUGCACACUGACCGCAGUGCUGGGACGCCAGUUUUUGUCCCUGAACAAGGAGGUUACAAGGAAAAGUUUGUGAAGACCGUGGAGGACAAGUACAAGUGUGAGAAGUGCCACCUGGUGCUGUGCAGCCCGAAGCAGACCGAGUGUGGGCACCGCUUCUGCGAGAGCUGCAUGGCGGCCCUGCUGAGCUCUUCAAGUCCAAAAUGUACAGCGUGUCAAGAGAGCAUCGUUAAAGAUAAGGUGUUUAAGGAUAAUUGCUGCAAGAGAGAAAUUCUGGCUCUUCAGAUCUAUUGUCGGAAUGAAAGCAGAGGUUGUGCAGAGCAGUUAAUGCUGGGACAUCUGCUGGUGCAUUUAAAAAAUGAUUGCCAUUUUGAAGAACUUCCAUGUGUGCGUCCUGACUGCAAAGAAAAGGUCUUGAGGAAAGACCUGCGAGACCACGUGGAGAAGGCGUGUAAAUACCGGGAAGCCACAUGCAGCCACUGCAAGAGUCAGGUUCCGAUGAUCGCGCUGCAGAAACACGAAGACACCGACUGUCCCUGCGUGGUGGUGUCCUGCCCUCACAAGUGCAGCGUCCAGACUCUCCUGAGGAGCGAGUUGAGUGCACACUUGUCAGAGUGUGUCAAUGCCCCCAGCACCUGUAGUUUUAAGCGCUAUGGCUGCGUUUUUCAGGGGACAAACCAGCAGAUCAAGGCCCACGAGGCCAGCUCCGCCGUGCAGCACGUCAACCUGCUGAAGGAGUGGAGCAACUCGCUCGAAAAGAAGGUUUCCUUGUUGCAGAAUGAAAGUGUAGAAAAAAACAAGAGCAUACAAAGUUUGCACAAUCAGAUAUGUAGCUUUGAAAUUGAAAUUGAGAGACAAAAGGAAAUGCUUCGAAAUAAUGAAUCCAAAAUCCUUCAUUUACAGCGAGUGAUAGACAGCCAAGCAGAGAAACUGAAGGAGCUUGACAAGGAGAUCCGGCCCUUCCGGCAGAACUGGGAGGAAGCAGACAGCAUGAAGAGCAGCGUGGAGUCCCUCCAGAACCGCGUGACCGAGCUGGAGAGCGUGGACAAGAGCGCGGGGCAAGUGGCUCGGAACACAGGCCUGCUGGAGUCCCAGCUGAGCCGGCAUGACCAGAUGCUGAGUGUGCACGACAUCCGCCUAGCCGACAUGGACCUGCGCUUCCAGGUCCUGGAGACCGCCAGCUACAAUGGAGUGCUCAUCUGGAAGAUUCGCGACUACAAGCGGCGGAAGCAGGAGGCCGUCAUGGGGAAGACCCUGUCCCUUUACAGCCAGCCUUUCUACACUGGUUACUUUGGCUAUAAGAUGUGUGCCAGGGUCUACCUGAACGGGGACGGGAUGGGGAAGGGGACGCACUUGUCGCUGUUUUUUGUCAUCAUGCGUGGAGAAUAUGAUGCCCUGCUUCCUUGGCCGUUUAAGCAGAAAGUGACACUCAUGCUGAUGGAUCAGGGGUCCUCUCGACGUCAUUUGGGAGAUGCAUUCAAGCCCGACCCCAACAGCAGCAGCUUCAAGAAGCCCACUGGAGAGAUGAAUAUCGCCUCUGGCUGCCCAGUCUUUGUGGCCCAAACUGUUCUAGAAAAUGGGACAUAUAUUAAAGAUGAUACAAUUUUUAUUAAAGUCAUAGUGGAUACUUCGGAUCUGCCCGAUCCCUGAUAAGUAGCUGGGGAGGUGGAUUUAGCAGAAGGCAACUCCUCUGGGGGAUUUGAACCGGUCUGUCUUCACUGAGGUCCUCGCGCUCAGAAAAGGACCUUGUGAGACGGAGGAAGCGGCAGAAGGCGGACGCGUGCCGGCGGGAGGAGCCACGCGUGAGCACACCUGACACGUUUUAUAAUAGACUAGCCACACUUCACUCUGAAGAAUUAUUUAUCCUUCAACAAGAUAAAUAUUGCUGUCAGAGAAGGUUUUCAUUUUCAUUUUUAAAGAUCUAGUUAAUUAAGGUGGAAAACAUAUAUGCUAAACAAAAGAAACAUGAUUUUUCUUCCUUAAACUUGAACACCAAAAAAACACACACACACACACACGUGGGGAUAGCUGGACAUGUCAGCAUGUUAAGUAAAAGGAGAAUUUAUGAAAUAGUAAUGCAAUUCUGAUAUCUUCUUUCUAAAAUUCAAGAGUGCAAUUUUGUUUCAAAUACAGUAUAUUGUCUAUUUUUAAGGCCUCAUCUGGUCUCUGUUUUAAUAAUUUGUUUGUCAGAAGACCCUGAAGUAUAUACCUAGGUCUUUUUUUUGAAAGUCUCUAAAUUCAGAAUCAUUUUUUAAUUUAAAGUUCUACAAAUAAUUGUUACUGCAAACAUUUUAUUUUAAAACGUUGAUAGACUGAUAUUUCUUGGAAGAAAAUAUAAAAUAUCAAACACUGGUUAUCACUUGUGAUAGGAAAGAGAAUAUUCAACCUGUUGUUAUUUCUCGUUAGAAAUGUAAACCUUCAAAUAUCUGUCGUAGUUAAUGACACGACUUCACAAUUCUGAACGGAGCCUCGCUCAUGGAUGCUGUGCAUCAUUUUCAGAUUUAUAAUUGUUUUCACCCUAAAAUAGGGCAUCCGUUGAACUUUGGAGUUCUAAACAAAAUCCUGUAGGUGUUUGGAUUCUGCCCCAUGUGUUCGGACGAGCUCUCUGUUGCUGACAGCACCGGCCUUCGGUCUCCAUGUCAGGGGUGGGCGGGUGACUGCUGAGGGAGGCCCGCAGGUGUGUUUCUCCAUCCCGUCAUCUUGCUGCAUGCCGUCAACGGUCUCCGAAAGCAACGUUGUGCGUAGAGCUGGUGGCAUACGGCCCACGUGCCUUAGAUGGGACAUGCUGCUUCUCCACCCUGGGUUUGCAUUGAGCAUCAUUCUAGAAAGUGCUAGUUUAACCAGACUUUUCUCUCCACCACUAGAUCUUUGUCUCUACAAGGGCCCUCAGACACCUCUGCACCUGCUGAGGGGAAGCCAGGCUCCACCGUCGGCUUCUGGAGCCUCCGCUGCUUAAUUACCACAGAUUCCAAAUCUCUAGGCCCCACGAGUGAGCCGCCUGGUCCAAGUACGGCCUGGUCCCACCCUGAGGGAGGCAGGUGUGGAACAGAAGCCGAGCCUCUCCGUGUCCCCACCGGGGCCGUGGGCACCCCCACAGCCCGAAGCAGAACCCUCUGAGCAUUCCAGAGACCGCUGCUCGGGGGCCUGCCCAGGCUGACCAACGGGCGCUCCUGACCACCACCCUGGCGGGAAGGGUGGCCACGGGGCCCGUCGUCCCAGCCUGUGCCUGCCCAGAUGGCAUUUUCUCAACUCACUGUUUACUGUCUCUCAGUGUCCAACUGUGAUUAGAAGCCUGGAGCCUGCCCCCUGCACCCCUUUUGCUAUGCACCACGCUUCAUGGUGCUCUUACCACUGAUGGGUGCUACACGCGACGGGUGCUUCUUAGGCAAAACCAAUGUGUGCGAACUGUCACACCUGUGCCACUCGCCCACAAGCCGCGCCCACAAUUGGCCAGCUGGGCCGUGCACGUCAGACUGCCUGCCUCGGCUCUCCCCGUGGCCGCGCGGGGACAGCUUGGUGGGUGCCCGGUGGCCCACCUGUCUCUGGUGCUGCCAUCUGUCCUGGGUGUGCCUUCGCCCCAGUGCCUGCUGGAAGUGCCCUCCGUCGCACCCCUGUGCCCUGAGCUCCCGUGAGGGGCCCGCCGCGCCCUUUCGCGGUCGAAGCGUUCCGUUGUUCUUAUCUGCCUUUCCUUUCCCCGCUCUCCUGGGAUUACUUUGGGGGAAUGAGUAUCCUUGGUUCUGCCCUGUGAGGGAGUCGUGUGUCCCUGCUCAUAAAGGAAGGACUUCCUGCAGAAGCUGCGGAAAACUACUGUUCCCUCGAAGGUGUCCCCCACCUGAGGCCUGUCCCCUACCUGCCCUCAGGUAGUUUUCCUGAGGCCAGGGGUUAACAACAGGGACAUCCCUGCAACUUCCCCUUCACAAAAUGUAUAAUAUUAGAUGAAGGAUAUGCAACAUCUUGGUCUAGUAAGAACCGUUUCCUCCCCUCUGGGUUGAAGUCCUGGUGUGGCCCCCAGAAGCAGCAGUGCGUGUCACUGGGACGUCUCCAGUAGCCCUUCCCAGGCAGACGCUCCUGGCGGGACGCCAUGGGGCCCACCUGAGGGUCCCACAGACGUAACCUGAGUGACAGGAGUCCUUGAGGAUGGGAUGGCCUAUGUCACACACUUUGUCCUUGAACCUGAGUGAUGGGGGUCCUUGAGGAUGGGAUGGCCUGUGUCACGCGCUUUGUCUUUGUGUUUGGUUGUAUCGGGGUCUCUGUUCUGAGUGUGUCUUCCUCUCAUGUACUCAACACAGUGGGCAGCAGCCUGGGACGGCGUCCCCUCUCCCGGCGGCGGGCAAGCCUUGCGCUGCUCCACCCUCGGCCUGGGCACCCUCACUUGGCGCUGGCCACCUGGGCCAGCCUGGGGCCAUGGUCUCUCUGCAGCUGAGGCCCAGUGGCCCCUUGGGCAGUGAUCGGCCCUCCCCGCAUCACAGGGCCCUGGCAGCAAGCGGGAAAUGGGGGCGCACACUGUGUGCUUGGGGGUGCUGCUUGUUUACCACACAUGACCAGACUCCCAGCAGGACAGAGCUGCUCAGUACUUUACAGAAACCAACUGAGUCGUUUGUGCAUGAAUUAAGCCGGUCUGCUUCCCCGUCACCUUCGUAACAAAACAACGUCCCCUCUCCCCUCGCCUCGAGCAGUUUCUUCAGGACACCGUGGCUCGGGCUGCUCCCUGCUGCCAGGCACGCUGGUUGGCUGGCCUGGGCCCGGCUCACGUGAAGGGCACUGGCUCUUGUGACCACACUGAGCCACGUGCAAGCCGCAGCCGGGCCUGGAAGCCUGACCCUCUGGUUCUAGGGCUUGUCCCGCGGAGCCUGCAGAGCUAGACGUUGGGGUGUGUCCGUGAUGAUAUGGGGGCCAGGCUGGGAGUAGGGCCUUUCUAGCAGGGUUGGGUGGCUCAGUGAGGGUGUGGAAGUGGGGGACCCACGGGGCCUGGCUUUGGGACUAGACAUGCCAGCCCCAGCUGGGCUGGAGGGAGCCUGAGUGAGCCCCGACAUACGCUGGGCCUUUCAGCUCGCCGUGCUCUGGUGACACACAGGCGGCCAGGUUGGGAUUUGUGUCAAUUCUAGGAGCCAUCAAGCAUGAAUGUGGUUCUGUCUCCUGAGCGCAAGCCUCGCCGGACCCCUGGGCGAAGGCCUGGACUUGCAGAUGUGUGUUCCCUGUGCGGGUGGACAGAGGGGGCCCUUAUGACCCACAUUGCAGCCCCAUUCCACCACCCCUUCCUCCCCAGAGCAGUCUCUGCCGAGGGACAGCACCUGUGUCCCUUCGAUGCCACAACAGCCAGUUGAACAGGGGAGCCCUUUGCUCAGGCAGCUUCUCCUGCCUCUCCCUCCUUUCUCCUUCCCUGCCCCAUCCCCGUGCCCUUCUUGGCCUGUGGCGCUGGGGAGCCAUGGUGUGGCAUACUGGGGCUCCUGCUCCUUGGGCCACUUCCUCAGCCCGGGCCCCACAGGCCCACCACCUGCCAGGGCUCCCACUGCACUGGCUGUGGCAGGAGGCUUCCCCAUGACCCCGUGUGGCCCAGCUCGGUGAGGAUGCAGUUCUAGGCACAGCCCCUGGGACAGCCAGCUGCCUCCCAGACCACGUCAGCCUGCUCCAGGGUCCUCAGUCACCCUGGGCCAGGGGCCACGUGUCCCAUGGAUGUCGACCAUGCCAACGUCACAUUCCAGCACCCCUUUUGCUUGAUGGCGUCUGGUGGUAGUCAGCAUGGUGGACCCACAUCCUACAGCCAGAGGUGAUGUUGGACAAAGGAAGGGGAGUCUGGAUGGGUCCUUAAACGACCAUUCUGUCCGCAGCGGGGUCAUUCCUUGUCAGCCCAAGGGAGGGCCGGGGAGUACACUGAUCCCAACAGCUGGGCUGACACCUCCUUUCUCCCCUGCACGGGGAGGAUUGGCCUGAGGACCGUCACCCUGUGCACAGCCCCAGUAGGGUGGCAGUGCCACUGUCUCCUUGGGCCGUUGCAGGAUUGGGCGGGUGCAGACUCCCCUUGCGGGCCCCUUGCUCAAUCCCCGGCCCUCCCAGACUCCUCCCUCUACUGGGGGUAAUUUGUGUGUCAGAAGGGCUCUGGCAGAGCUGUAAAAUACUGUUUUUUAAAAAUUUUAGUCCAGAUCUUUACUUAUUAGACUGCAGAAGGAGAGCUAGGGAGAGUGGGGGAAGCCCCCUUGCUUUUGUAUCUGUGAGGUGAAUGAGGGUCUGUCACCCAAAUCUACUUCUCAGCCCAUGACCAUAGUUCUGUUUUCCGUUUGCAAAUCUCAGUAGCUCUGUUUUCUCCAAAGUAGAAUGUGCGCACCGGGGUCCUAGCCAGGCGAGGUCAGUGUCGGCAGGCUACCUGGUCAUUAUUGCUGCCUCGUCCAGGCUGAUGCUGAUGGUCACAGGCACGGUGGCAUCAGGGAGCCGGGCCAGCAGGCGGCGUGAGGCGGGGCCAGCAGCUCACUGCAAGGGCAUUUUCCACCUGAUCCUGGUGUGCCCCACAUGCGGUGGCAGGGCAGACGUGUGAAGCCUCGGCCGUCUCGGGGCUGGCAGGUGUGCGGGUGAGGAGGCCCCGGUGGCCAAGCAGAGCCUGCGUUUCAUUUCUCCUGCUGCACUGUGUCUAGUCUGUCUUGUGAACUCUCACCGUGAAAAGAGGCUAGAAGUCCAGGAUCGCUGUACCGCUCCUGUAAUUAGGUGAUGACUGGAUUUGACAACUUAGUCCCCUCAGACAAGUAAGAUACCCUCCAACAGCAAAUUCAAUGACUUAAUUGGAAAACACACAAGCUGGCAUGAUGUCCGGUGAUUUCUGUAAGAAAUGCCUGUAGGAGAAGGUCUGUGAAGUGUGGAGGGCAGUGUCGACGCUGCACAGCAUCUGCAGAUUCGCAGCCUCUUCUCUGCCGGUGCCUCUGUUCGGUUCUGUUACCCAAAAACAAAGACCAAAGAAGGCCAAUCUCUCAUUUGACCCUGUCUUUUUAAUCUGCCUGUUUUAAAAGUUGCGUCUGUAGUAGCCGCUUGCUGUGAAGACACAUCUUGACAGUCCAAGUGAUUUUGUGACCAGUGAUUUGGGUCCUGUUUUCCGCUCUUCUAAGAAAAAACAAAAAGACCGUGAGUUAUUGCCCAGCAAUAAUCAUGUUGUUACUGUGAGUUAGCAACAUGCCUGACUUCCUGAUAGCAUUACUGUUUUCUAGUUUUGUUUAUUGUAUAUUAUGUGUGGUUUUAUUUGGUAUUUAUUUGUGUUUUGAGGUCUUGCAAUGUUUUUGUGUUUCUGAUGCUAAUAACUAAAGUUUGUAAGACUGUAGAAUGCAAAACUCGGAGAUGCUAAACUGUCUUAUUAGAGGAAAAUAAAUCUGAUUAUGGAGUCUCA